AGCCAAGCCGGAGAGGAGGCGAGCAGCAGGGCCUGGUGGCGAGAGCGCGGCUGUCACUGCGCCCGAGCAUCCCAGAGCUUUCCGAGCGGACGAGCCGGCCGUGCCGGGCAUCCCCAGCCUCGCUACCCUCGCAGCACACGUCGAGCCCCGCACAGGCGAGGGUCCGGAACUUAGCCCAAAGCACGUUUCCCCUGGCAGCGCAGGAAACGCCCGGCCGCGCGCCGGCGCACGCCCCCCUCUCCUCCUUUGUUCCGGGGGUCGGCGGCCGCUCUCCUGCCAGCGUCGGGAUCUCGGCCCCGGGAGGCGGGCCGUCGGGCGCAGCCGCGAAGAUGCCGUUGGAACUGACGCAGAGCCGAGUGCAGAAGAUCUGGGUGCCCGUGGACCACAGGCCCUCGUUGCCCAGAUCCUGUGGGCCAAAGCUGACCAACUCCCCCACCGUCAUCGUCAUGGUGGGCCUCCCCGCCCGGGGCAAGACCUACAUCUCCAAGAAGCUGACUCGCUACCUCAACUGGAUUGGCGUCCCCACAAAAGUGUUCAACGUCGGGGAGUAUCGCCGGGAGGCUGUGAAGCAGUACAGCUCCUACAACUUCUUCCGCCCCGACAAUGAGGAAGCCAUGAAAGUCCGGAAGCAAUGUGCCUUAGCUGCCUUGAGAGAUGUCAAAAGCUACCUGGCGAAAGAAGGGGGACAAAUUGCGGUUUUCGAUGCCACCAAUACUACUAGAGAGAGGAGACACAUGAUCCUUCAUUUUGCCAAAGAAAAUGACUUUAAGGCGUUUUUCAUCGAGUCGGUGUGCGACGACCCUACAGUUGUGGCCUCCAAUAUCAUGCAGAAAGCCUUCCAGCGUGAUUUAUCAGCCACCCCUUUGUGGUGUUGCAGGAAGUUAAAAUCUCCAGCCCGGAUUACAAAGACUGCAACUCGGCAGAAGCCAUGGACGACUUCAUGAAGAGGAUCAGUUGCUAUGAAGCCAGCUACCAGCCCCUCGACCCCGACAAAUGCGACAGGGACUUGUCGCUGAUCAAGGUGAUUGACGUGGGCCGGAGGUUCCUGGUGAACCGGGUGCAGGACCACAUCCAGAGCCGCAUCGUGUACUACCUGAUGAACAUCCACGUGCAGCCGCGUACCAUCUACCUGUGCCGGCACGGCGAGAACGAGCACAACCUCCAGGGCCGCAUCGGGGGCGACUCAGGCCUGUCCAGCCGGGGCAAGAAGUUUGCCAGUGCUCUGAGCAAGUUCGUGGAGGAGCAGAACCUGAAGGACCUGCGCGUGUGGACCAGCCAGCUGAAGAGCACCAUCCAGACGGCCGAGGCGCUGCGGCUGCCCUACGAGCAGUGGAAGGCGCUCAAUGAGAUCGACGCGGGCGUCUGUGAGGAGCUGACCUACGAGGAGAUCAGGGACACCUACCCUGAGGAGUAUGCGCUGCGGGAGCAGGACAAGUACUAUUACCGCUACCCCACCGGGGAGUCCUACCAGGACCUGGUCCAGCGCUUGGAGCCAGUGAUCAUGGAGCUGGAGCGGCAGGAGAAUGUGCUGGUCAUCUGCCACCAGGCCGUCCUGCGCUGCCUGCUUGCCUACUUCCUGGAUAAGAGUGCAGAGGAGAUGCCCUACCUGAAAUGCCCUCUUCACACCGUCCUGAAACUGACGCCUGUCGCUUAUGGCUGCCGUGUGGAAUCCAUCUACCUGAACGUGGAGUCCGUCUGCACACACCGGGAGAGGUCAGAGGAUGCAAAGAAGGGACCUAACCCGCUCAUGAGACGCAAUAGUGUCACCCCGCUAGCCAGCCCCGAACCCACCAAAAAGCCUCGCAUCAACAGCUUUGAGGAGCAUGUGGCCUCCACCUCGGCCGCCCUGCCCAGCUGCCUGCCCCCGGAGGUGCCCACGCAGCUGCCUGGACAAAACAUGAAAGGCUCCCGGAGCAGCGCUGACUCCUCCAGGAAACACUGAGGCAGACGUGUCGGUUCCAUUCCAUUUCCAUUUCUGCAGCUUAGCUUGUGUCCUGCCCUCCGCCCGAGGCAAAACGUAUCCUGAGGACUUCUUCCGGAGAGGGUGGGGUGGAGCAGCGGGGGAGCCUUGGCCGAAGAGAACCAUGCUUGGCACCGUCUGUGUCCCCUCGGCCGCUGGACACCAGAAAGCCACGUGGGUCCCUGGCGCCCUGCCUUUAGCCGUGGGGCCCCCACCUCCACUCUCUGGGUUUCCUAGGAAUGUCCAGCCUCGGAGACCUUCACAAAGCCUUGGGAGGGUGAUGAGUGCUGGUCCUGACAGGAGGCCGCUGGGGACACUGUGCUGUUUUGUUUCGUUUCUGUGAUCUCCCGGCACGUUUGGAGCUGGGAAGACCACACUGGUGGCAGAAUCCUAAAAUUAAAGGAGGCAGGCUCCUAGUUGCUGAAAGUUAAGGAAUGUGUAAAACCUCCACGUGACUGUUUGGUGCAUCUUGACCUGGGAAGACGCCUCAUGGGAACGAACUUGGACAGGUGUUGGGUUGAGGCCUCUUCUGCAGGAAGUCCCUGAGCUGAGACGCAAGUUGGCUGGGUGGUCCGCACCCUGGCUCUCCUGCAGGUCCACACACCUUCCAGGCCUGUGGCCUGCCUCCAAAGAUGUGCAAGGGCAGGCUGGCUGCACGGGGAGAGGGAAGUAUUUUGCCGAAAUAUGAGAACUGGGGCCUCCUGCUCCCAGGGAGCUCCAGGGCCCCUCUCUCCUCCCACCUGGACUUGGGGGGAACUGAGAAACACUUUCCUGGAGCUGCUGGCUUUUGCACUUUUUUGAUGGCAGAAGUGUGACCUGAGAGUCCCACCUUCUCUUCAGGAACGUAGAUGUUGGGGUGUCUUGCCCUGGGGGGCUUGGAACCUCUGAAGGUGGGGAGCGGAACACCUGGCAUCCUUCCCCAGCACUUGCAUUACCGUCCCUGCUCUUCCCAGGUGGGGACAGUGGCCCAAGCAAGGCCUCACUCGCAGCCACUUCUUCAAGAGCUGCCUGCACACUGUCUUGGAGCAUCUGCCUUGUGCCUGGCACUCUGCCGGUGCCUUGGGAAGGUCGGAAGAGUGGACUUUGUCCUGGCCUUCCCUUCAUGGCGUCUAUGACACUUUUGUGGUGAUGGAAAGCAUGGGACCUGUCGUCUCAGCCUGUUGGUUUCUCCUCAUUGCCUCAAACCCUGGGGUAGGUGGGACGGGGGGUCUCGUGCCCAGAUGAAACCAUUUGGAAACUCGGCAGCAGAGUUUGUCCAAAUGACCCUUUUCAGGAUGUCUCAAAGCUUGUGCCAAAGGUCACUUUUCUUUCCUGCCUUCUGCUGUGAGCCCUGAGAUCCUCCUCCCAGCUCAAGGGACAGGUCCUGGGUGAGGGUGGGAGAUUUAGACACCUGAAACUGGGCGUGGAGAGAAGAGCCGUUGCUGUUUGUUUUUUGGGAAGAGCUUUUAAAGAAUGCAUGUUUUUUUCCUGGUUGGAAUUGAGUAGGAACUGAGGCUGUGCUUCAGGUAUGGUACAAUCAAGUGGGGGAUUUUCAUGCUGAACCAUUCAAGCCCUCCCCGCCCGUUGCACCCACUUUGGCUGGCGUCUGCUGGAGAGGAUGUCUCUGUCCGCAUUCCCGUGCAGCUCCAGGCUCGCGCAGUUUUCUCUCUCUCCCUGGAUGUUGAGUCUCAUCAGAAUAUGUGGGUAGGGGGUGGACGUGCACGGGUGCAUGAUUGUGCUUAACUUGGUUGUAUUUUUCGAUUUGACAUGGAAGGCCUGUUGCUUUGCUCUUGAGAAUAGUUUCUCGUGUCCCCCUCGCAGGCCUCAUUCUUUGAACAUCGACUCUGAAGUUUGAUACAGAUAGGGGCUUGAUAGCUGUGGUCCCCUCUCCCCUCUGACUACCUAAAAUCAAUACCUAAAUACAGAAGCCUUGGUCUAACACGGGACUUUUAGUUUGCGAAGGGCCUAGAUAGGGAGAGAGGUAACAUGAAUCUGGACAGGGAGGGAGAUACUAUAGAAAGGAGAACACUGCCUACUUUGCAAGCCAGUGACCUGCCUUUUGAGGGGACAUUGGACGGGGGCCGGGGGCGGGGGUUGGGUUUGAGCUACAGUCAUGAACUUUUGGCGUCUACUGAUUCCUCCAACUCUCCACCCCACAAAAUAACGGGGACCAAUAUUUUUAACUUUGCCUAUUUGUUUUUGGGUGAGUUUCCCCCCUCCUUAUUCUGUCCUGAGACCACGGGCAAAGCUCUUCAUUUUGAGAGAGAAGAAAAACUGUUUGGAACCACACCAAUGAUAUUUUUCUUUGUAAUACUUGAAAUUUAUUUUUUUAUUAUUUUGAUAGCAGAUGUGCUAUUUAUUUAUUUAAUAUGUAUAAGGAGCCUAAACAAUAGAAAGCUGUAGAGAUUGGGUUUCAUUGUUAAUUGGUUUGGGAGCCUCCUAUGUGUGACUUAUGACUUCUCUGUGUUCUGUGUAUUUGUCUGAAUUAAUGACCUGGGAUAUAAAGCUAUGCUAGCUUUCAAACAGGAGAUGCCUUUCAGAAAUUUGUAUAUUUUGCAGUUGCCAGACCAAUAAAAUACCUGGUUGAAAUACA